AGGAUGUCUCCCUUCUGACUUCCCCUUAGCAACCAAGUCGCGGCGCUUGGUUCCCCAGCAACCGGGAGACGCGUCUGCUGCGUGGAACCGCCGAGUUCCCAGCGCUUGAGAAGGUGAGACCUGGGAGCUGAGGCUCCCGGAGGACUUGCAGGGACAGAUAGUGCCCGACGUAACUCUUUCCUGUGACCUUUUUCUCGGAGAACGCCGGCCCGGCCCUUCUCAUUUAUAAAAUGAGCACGAAAAUUCUGGAUCUGUUAUCUGUGAGGAGGCCACUCCGUUGACAGUUGUGUAAAACUCUGCUGCUUUCCCCAGCUCCAACCUCUCUGGUCUUCAACAACACUAUCAUCAGGGAAAACGUGGGGGAAGAUGAACCAGCCGUGCAACUCGAUGGAGCCGAGGGUGAUGGACGAUGACAUGCUCAAGCUGGCCGUCGGGGACCAGGGCCCCCAGGAGGAGGCCGGGCAGCUGGCCAAGCAGGAGGGCAUCCUCUUCAAGGAUGUCCUGUCCCUGCAGCUGGACUUUCGGAGAAAAACAGCAGAUGAACCCAAAGGGGAACAGGAUGAUGGCCAGGAGGAUUCCCAGGAAGACAUCCUCCGCAUAGACAACCUCUGGCAGUUUGAGAACUUGAGGAAGCUGCAGCUGGACAAUAACAUCAUUGAGAAGAUCGAGGGCCUGGAGAACCUCGCACACCUGGUCUGGCUGGAUCUGUCUUUCAACAACAUUGAGACCAUCGAGGGGCUGGACACACUGGUGAACCUGGAGGACCUGAGCUUGUUCAACAACCGGAUCUCCAAGAUCGACUCCCUGGACGCCCUCGUCAAGCUGCAGGUGUUGUCGCUGGGCAACAACCGGAUUGACAACAUGAUGAACAUCAUCUACCUCCGGCGGUUCAAGUGCCUGCGGACGCUCAGCCUCUCUAGGAACCCUAUCUCUGAGGCAGAGGAUUACAAGAUGUUCAUCUGUGCCUACCUUCCUGACCUCAUGUACCUGGACUACCGGCGCAUUGAUGACCACACAGCAAGUGUCUCCCUCUCAGUCUCCCAGCCCUGUGAGACAGAUUCCUCAAGCCCCCAGAAAAAGCUUGCGGAGGCUAAGCACCAGUACAGCAUCGACGAGCUGAAGCACCAGGAGAACCUGAUGCAGGCCCAGCUGGAGGACGAGCAGGCGCAGCGGGAGGAGCUAGAGAAGCACAAGACUGCGUUUGUGGAACACCUGAAUGGCUCCUUCCUGUUUGACAGCAUGUACGCUGAGGACUCAGAGGGCAACAAUCUGUCCUACCUGCCUGGUGUCGGUGAGCUCCUUGAGACCUACAAGGACAAGUUUGUCAUCAUCUGCGUGAAUAUUUUUGAGUAUGGCCUGAAACAGCAGGAGAAGCGGAAAACAGAGCUUGACACCUUCAGUGAAUGUGUCCGUGAGGCCAUCCAGGAAAACCAGGAGCAGGGCAAACGCAAGAUUGCCAAAUUCGAGGAGAAGCACUUGUCGAGUUUAAGUGCCAUUCGAGAGGAGUUGGAACUGCCCAACAUUGAGAAGAUGAUCCUAGAAUGCAGUGCUGACAUCAGUGAGUUGUUCGAUGCGCUCAUGACGCUGGAGAUGCAGCUGGUGGAGCAGCUGGAGGAGACUAUAAACAUGUUUGAAAGGAACAUUGUUGACAUGGUAGGACUGUUUAUCGAAAAUGUCCAAAGCCUGAUGGCUCAGUGCCGGGACCUGGAGAAUCACCACCACGAGAAGCUCCUGGAGAUCUCUAUCAGCACCCUGGAGAAGAUUGUCGAGGGCGACCUGGACGAGGACCUGCCUAACGACCUGCGCGCGCUUUUUGUCGAUAAAGAUACGAUUGUUAAUGCUGUCGGGGCAUCGCACGACAUCCACCUCCUGAAGAUUGACAAUCGAGAAGAUGAGCUGGUGACCAGAAUCAACUCUUGGUGUACACGUUUAAUAGACAGGAUUCACAAGGAUGAGAUCAUGAGGAACCGCAAGCGCGUGAAGGAGAUCAAUCAGUACAUCGACCACAUGCAGAGCGAACUGGACAACCUGGAAUGUGGCGACAUCCUAGACUAGAUGAAUGUCAGCCACAGGAGCUUCUUCAAAACAUAGCACCAGCCCCAGCCAGGAGAAGGAAGUGCACACGCCUCACCCGCACCUCUAGAGAGUUGCUGGGCAUCUCUCAACCGCGAUCCCCAACACCAUUCUUCCCCCACCCCUGGAAAAACUUCCAAAAGUAGAGAAAAUAAAGGACUCAUUUCACAUUUCCCCUACUCAUAAAAAAAAAAAAAAAA